GCCGCUGGCUUCCGGUCCCCUGAGACUGGGGCCUCGCUCGCUCCCGACCCGGUUGCAAGUGUUGCGGUGGGAGAAAGUCGCGUCCGCAUCGGAGGGGAAGCGCCGUCAUGCCUAAGUAUUAUGAGGACAAGCCGCAGGGCGGCGCGUGCGCGGGCCUGAAGGAGGACCUGGGCGCGUGUCUGCUGCAGUCGGACUGUGUGGUCCAGGAAGGAAAAUCACCUCGGCAGUGUUUGAAGGAAGGAUACUGCAACUCUUUGAAGUACGCAUUUUUUGAGUGUAAAAGAUCAGUGUUGGAUAACAGGGCAAGAUUCAGAGGAAGAAAAGGAUAUUGAUGCAUUAUGUUGAAGCCAACAUGGAAAACAACAAAUAUUUUCCCUGGUCAUUAACACAAAGAAGCCAAAACAGGAAACAUACUUUUUACUACAUCUGUUUGGUUGGACCAGAUUUCCCCUCCGUGGAACACUGAAGAAAGUGGAUGAGUUGUUUUCGAAUAUGUAUAAAGUAAAUGAUUCUCUUGAUCCAAGUUAUUUUUAGAAGAAAAACCUAAUUGAACAGGUAUGGGUUGGGAGCAUAAUAAAUGUGUUUUGAGAAUUGUUCUAAAGCACAGAAAAUGGAAAGACUGUUAUUUGCAAACUUGACUCUUCAAUUGAAUUACCCAAUUAGUACAGGCCACUGAUUUGACUGACACAGUCGAUAACAUGCAGCCUAUCCAGAAGGUGUCUGUUGGGAAAGUUUAGGAUAAAACUUUUUCUUUAGUUCAGUCUUUUCCUGUCUAGUUCUAAAAUGAAUUGUGUUUGAUUCCUUAGAGAAGAAAUACUUCAUUUGUGCUCUGAUUCACUGAAGUAAUAACCUCAGCACUUUAAUAGCGUCCACAGGCAUAGCUGAUGCUAGGCCCCAGAUUGUGUUGCCCAGGCUCUUUACCAUCAUCUUCGGACUGUUUUUGUUUCCUGGUUACAUUUUCAGUCUGGCCCGCUCUACAUAAUGGGCCAGUGUCAGCUCCAAGUCCACAUCCUUAUUAUCCAUGAUUCAAAAGGGAGAGAGAGAACUUCCUUUUUCAGGGUCCACAAAUCAAAUCUAUAAAAGGACUCUGGUCUUCCCAGGAUCACCUGCCCUUGCAUUGGACCAGUCCCUGUGGAAGAGGGGAUGGGGGCCUGUGAUCUUGGCCAGGCCUGGGCUAUCUAUCUGCACUGUCAUUGCUAACUCCUGUCAGAAUCACAUGGAUGAGUAGUGGGCUGAAUCCCAAAAGGAAAGGGGUUUAGAGCAAGUGGAAACAACAGAUGUUCACUAUAGAAAGCAAGAAUGAAAACCAUGAAGUGGUUGAAGAUUAGCCUUACAGUAAUUUUAUUCUGAUCACUUAAUACAGUAGAGUCAAACAGGAAUCCAAGUUUCCAACUUUAUUAUUUUUGGCACUGAAGAAUUACAAAGAACUCUAGCGUCUUUAUACCUCCGUGGUUCACUGGAGUUAAAGCAAUCGGGGCGUUGUACAGCUCACUUGAGUUUUUAAAGGUUCUACUAAAAAGUGAGAAUUCCACAGCAAUAUGGGUCAUUGUUGCAGAAUAUCACAAAGGUCUGUUGUGUAUACUCCUUUUCACCAGGAAAGGGACAAUAAUAGUUUUUUUCAAUGUAUAUAUAUAUAAGUGAUCUAACUUUUUAUUAAUAAAAGUAAACAACUCUAAAAUGUAUAUUAUAAAGCCCUGUCAUCUUUGUUGAGUAAUAGCUUUAUUGAGCUUUAUUUGGAGAAAUACACAUACCGUAAAAUUCACACUGAAA